AGUUAGUUACGAGUCGGCGCACGCGGCCUCGGUCCGGUUGACUUUGCGGAGCCAUGGAGGGCGGCUUCGGCUCCGAUUUCGGGGGCUCCGGCAGCGGGAAGCUGGACCCAGGGCUCAUAAUGGAGCAGGUGAAAGUGCAGAUCGCCGUGGCCAACGCGCAGGAGCUGCUGCAGAGGAUGACGGACAAGUGUUUCCGGAAGUGUAUAGGGAAACCUGGGGGCUCCCUGGACAACUCCGAGCAGAAGUGCAUCGCCAUGUGCAUGGACCGCUACAUGGACGCCUGGAACACCGUGUCUCGCGCCUACAACUCGCGGCUGCAGCGGGAACGAGCCAACAUGUGACCGGCGAGCGCGGGCCACCCCACCCUGUUCAUUUCCAUAAACGUGCUUUGAGAGGCGGGGUCCGCAUGUACGUACUGCCUGCCCGGGGCUUAGGAGGGUGGCACCGGUGCUGGGACACACGGGACUGUGUCCUCGCCACCCCCCGCCCUGCCCCCUGCCAGCCAGUGCAGCUUGGAUCUCGGGGGUGUGGGGCCCUGUGCCUUCCUGAAGUGCUGGCAGCCCAGUGGCACCUCCUUCAGGCCUUUGGGGUAUUCCCCUAGUGUGCCCAAGUCAGCCUCAUAUUCUGGGCGGACAGCUUGUCUGGACUUCGGAGUUGGGGGUGGUCAGACACCACAGGAGCUGUCACCUCCUGCGGAUGGGCAAAUAAAUUGGUGGAGGACGGAGAGAAACCUCUUUAUUUCCCUCCUGAGGGGUCUCUGGGAAGAGGUGACGCGUGUCCCUGGAACCCCAGCUCGGAGGGUCUCAGCCUCCCCUGGGUUGGGAGAAGUCCAUCUUUCCCCUUAGUGCCACCGGGCUGCUGAGUCACGAGGAAUGUGUUGCUGCUGCCACCCCUGCCCCAAAGGCUAAGGGGGACAGCCUUCCCCUUGUCAGGGCUUGCUUUGACCCUGCUUCGUUCCACCCCGGGUCCUGGUGGAGCACCAGGCAGGUGGUCCUCGCUGUGACACUGAGGUGCUGAGCCAGUGAGCUAGGGUGGAGGGGCUGUGUUUAUUGGAACAAAGGGUGGUACCAAAAUGCAUCCCCAUGACCCACAGCCCCCCCACACCCGUCCUUGGGUAGGGUACGGUGGGGUGGGGUGUUGGGUGGCCUGCUGCUCCUGUUGCUUUCACGUAGAGUCUCGGCCUGGGCAGUCACGUGGUGGUCACUCCUGGAUGUGCUGUCCUAUCCAGCCUCUCACAGCUGCCACCCGGGUAUAGACACCUGGGAAGUGGGGCCGGCCACAGCCAUAGCCCCAGCUAGUGACCCCAGUUAGCACCCACCGUCCAGAGGGCUCCCUGCAGGCCAGGGGUCCCCCAGCGUCACCCUGUUGGGGAGAGAAGAAAGGGGGUUCAGAGGCCGGUACCUCCCCUACAGCAGCCCUUGGGUCAUUGGCCCCUCUAGGAGUGACCCUAGUGACUUCCCCUGGGAGCCGCAUUUUCACUAUCUGGAAAAUGGGCUCAAUGCAAAGGUGGCAGACAUUUAUGGACACCCGCCACGUGGUCCCGGAGUGGAACGGUGCCUCCCACUGCAGCCUCUGCCUGCUCUGCCGCCGAGGCCCGGGGAUGGGAUGCGGUGGGUUGCCCAAUAAACGGCUGUGGAGUGGAAAUUCCUCCAGAGCCAAAAAGG